GGCCCUGUUUCUUACUAGAGAGAGCUCUAUUUUCUUUUCUCUUUCCUUUGCCUAUUAAACCUCUGCUCCUGAACUCCUGGUGUGUGUCCGUGUCCUAAAUCUUCUUUGUGGGAGACAGUGAAUCCUGGAUAUUUACCCCAGACAGUGACACCACUUCAAUUGUAAAGUUUGCCAACAGAAAGAUCUGGCCUUUAGUAAGCACUCUAUAAAUGAAUAAAGAAGCAUUGAAAACAAGCCUCAGAAGACAUCUGGAAUCUUCGUGCGCCAGAUUGGAGGUAUAGAAUUACUCCUGCAAUAAUGGCAAAUCUCACAAUCGUGACUGAAUUUAUCCUUAUGGGGUUUUCUACCAAUAAAAAUAUGUGCAUUUUGCAUUCGAUUCUCUUCUUGUUGAUUUAUUUGUGUGCCCUGAUGGGGAAUGUCCUCAUUAUCAUGAUCACAACUUUGGACCAUCAUCUCCACACCCCCGUGUAUUUCUUCUUGAAGAAUCUAUCUUUCUUGGAUCUCUGCCUUAUUUCAGUCACGGCUCCCAAAUCUAUCGCCAAUUCUUUGAUACACAACAACUCCAUUUCAUUCCUUGGCUGUGUUUCCCAGGUCUUUUUGUUGCUUUCUUCAGCAUCUGCAGAGCUGCUCCUCCUCACGGUGAUGUCCUUUGACCGCUAUACUGCUAUAUGUCACCCUCUGCACUAUGAUGUCAUCAUGGACAGGAGCACCUGUGUCCAAAGAGCCACUGUGUCUUGGCUGUAUGGGGGUCUGAUUGCUGUGAUGCACACAGCUGGCACCUUCUCCUUAUCCUACUGUGGGUCCAACAUGGUCCAUCAGUUCUUCUGUGACAUUCCCCAGUUAUUAGCUAUUUCUUGCUCAGAAAAUUUAAUAAGAGAAAUUGCACUCAUCCUUAUUAAUGUAGUUUUGGAUUUCUGCUGUUUUAUUGUCAUCAUCAUUACCUAUGUCCACGUCUUCUCUACAGUCAAGAAGAUCCCUUCCACAGAAGGCCAGUCAAAAGCCUACUCUAUUUGCCUUCCACACUUGCUGGUUGUGUUAUUUCUUUCCACUGGAUUCAUUGCUUAUCUGAAGCCAGCUUCAGAGUCUCCUUCUAUUUUGGAUGCUGUAAUUUCUGUGUUCUACACUAUGCUGCCCCCAACCUUUAAUCCCAUUAUAUACAGUUUGAGAAACAAGGCCAUAAAGGUGGCUCUGGGGAUGUUGAUAAAGGGAAAGCUCACCAAAAAGUAAAAGCUGUUGCUUUUCUUCUUUCAAUAAUAGAUACCAUUUAUAAUGUACACACAUUAAUUCUUCAUUUUUAUCUCUAAUUCUUAAAAGUAAAAAUUUAAAAAGACAAAUGAAAGCAAUUAUUUUAUUAGAAAAUUUCCUUG